AAUUGAUGGUUUUGGCUCAAGCUUUGGAGGGACGAAGAAAUGGUGUGGAUUCUGUGAAAUCACAGGAUGUCUAAGUUCCAAGGGCUUUAGGAAUUGCCUCAUAUCGUGCGUCUAAAUAUUGCACCCCUGCCCCUCUUCCAGUCCAGACUCAUCCGAGAGGAUCAGCACAAUUCCAUUAGUAAAUGAAGUCACAACUUGGGGAUUGAUGGGGAUAAUUAAUAAAAAGGGCCACAAGUGGUUCCAAGUGCUCCUGCAGUCAUACACACACAUACUCUGUUUAGCAUCCCGAGUUCUCAGAGAAGGAAGAGGUGUGGAGAAGUUAUUUGAAUUUGUUAGUUCUCAGAUUUUUUUAUCAGGGUAAGCAGUUUUUAAAAAUUAAAGAGUGAAGAGAAAGUGAUGGACAUACACUUGCCAACUUUUAUUCAUUUGGACAUUUAAAAGGAAAAUCAUCACCAUAGAGUUAUAAAUAAAUUAUAACAAAUGUAACAAUAUAGCAUAUAUUUAGCUUUAUGAAAAACUGAUAUUGUCCUUCUCAUUUAACUAUAAAAAUUUCAUCACUGGCUGGAUGCUUGGUGGCUCAUGCCUGUAAUCCUAACACUUUGGGAGGCUGAGGAUUACAUGCCUGUAAUCCUAGCACUUUGGGAGGCCAAGGCAGGAGGAUCGCUUGAGCUCAGGAGUUCAGGACCAGUAAAACUCCAUCUCUACAAAAAAUACAAAAAUUUGUCCGGCAUGAUGGUAUAUUCCUGUAAUCCUAGCUCUUGGGAGGCUGAGGUGGGAGGAUCACUUGAGCCUAGGAGGUCGAGGCCACAGUGAGCUAUGAUUGUGCCACUGCACUCCAGUCUGGGUGACAGAGUGAGACCCUGUUUCAAUUUAAAAAAAAAGAUCACUUAGUUCGUUGUGUAGGAUUUAGGAAUUGCUAAUCAAGUAGUUAUAAUUAACUUGAAGAAUAAUUUAACAGUAUACAUUUUAAAUUUAAAACUAUGGUAUUAGCCUAUAUCAGCUCUAAGUGAAUUCUUGCCUGAUGCAAGAUGUGAUUCCUGCACAGCCACAGAGGGGUAUUUUUAAUUAAUUUAGGCUCAAUAAACUAAAGAAGCUUUUGGAAAAUUUGAACACAACUGAGAAAGCAACCCACAUCAGUUUCCGUAGGUACUCACAAAGCUGGGUGGUGGUGUACAUUGGUUAUAUUAUUUACAAAUACAAUUUUUGGGAGACUGUGGAAGGGAUAACUUGAAAUCUUGAAGAAUGAUUUAGGGCCUUGUUACCCAAAGUCUGAUCCAGGGACUAGCUACAUUAAUAGCACUUGGGAGCUGCUGGAAAUACAGGCCUCACCCCAGACCUGCUGGAUCAGAACCUGCAUUUUAACAAGAUCCCCAGGUGAUUCACAUGCAUAGCAGGUUUAAGAUACUGAUUUAGAGUACCUUUCUGAAAACAAGGGUUUCAGUUAGGUAACUUUCACAUAGCCUUUGCCUUAUCUAAUUAACAAGUGUUCCAAAACCAGGAUUAUUAGAAUAAAUAGGUUGUUGAGAAUAGCAAUUAAGACUAGCCUUAAAAAAAGGUAGUAUAGAAAGGCCUUGAGACCUGCAUUAAUGAUAAUAUAGCUUAUAAUUAGCUUAUCAAUUAAAUAUGCAUGGCUGUAUCUAAAGGGCUUGAAAACUGUUUUUAAGGUUUUUCUUUUCUAUCUUGAUUUUAUAUUUAGGAAAACCCAGGUAAACUCACAAAUAGAGGAACAUUUUUUUAAGCAGGAAAAUAUGUAACAAUUUUUGGGCCAAAUGCUUAAGAAGUGAGAAUUUUGAAAUGGAAACAAAAGUUGGAAUCUGUCUUAGAAGUAAUCUACUCCACCCCUUCUCUCCCAGCAGUUUGAGUGCUCUAUUUAAAGCUAGAAUUUUGAGCAUGAGAACGCCACUGUGGACAACAGAGAGAUUUUCUCUCUCUCUCACCUCUUCUCUUUCUCUCCUUCUAUCUCCCCCUCCACCACCAUCUCUCUCAUCUUCUUCCCUUUGUCCCCACCCCAUUGCUUUUUUCUUUCUGCUUUUCCUGUUCCCUAUCCUUACGCAGGAUUGUUUUACUGUUAGCCAGGUUAAGUUUAAGCUUCUUGAGGACUUUAGUACUGAAAGACAAUGGCUCACUUGUAAGACCUAGUUGAAGAGUACAGAUUUAGAUUUGUUCAGUGUGCUGUGAUCUGUAAAAAAAAAAAAUCACAAUGGGAUUUCUACUAAUGGAUAUGUAAAUAUAUAAUCAUUCCUUUUAUGCUUACAUCCAGGGUUUAAUUAAUCCUUUGGUAAUUAAGAAUCCCUUCAAAGUUUGCUUGUGAGCAUGUUGUUCCGACCAGCUAUUAGCUCCUAUACUAAAAUUGGUUGCCUUGCAGACCUGUGUUAUCAGUAAUAAGCACCUCAAAAGUCACUCAGGAGGAAAACCGAAUGGAAGACCUGAGCAGAGGGAAUCUUCAUUGUAUACCUUUUUGUGUCUUUUGAAUUGAGCCCUUUGAGUAUAUUAACUAAUCAAAUAAAUAGUUAAAUAAAAUUUAAAGAGAAAACUUUCUAAACUUUUUCACUAUGAGUGUGUGAUCUCUGAUGCCAGGUACUGUUUUGUGGAAGGGGAGAAAAUACUAGGUUUCGGUAGCAUCUUAACAAGUGAUAAAUGCUUUUGGCUUUAUUUCUCACUGACAUCUUGUACUUCUGGUGGUGUAUUUCUUCUUUCUACUGACCAGCAAGUAAGUUCCAAAAUACUGCUGAAUAUCAGGUUAGAAGAGAGCCAGUGUUUAUUUCCCACCCUGCAGUCUUCAGUGUAAAUAUCUGAAAAUGGUUAUAUUGGGAGAGACAAAAAGAUCUUCCAAAUCUCUCUUAUACAUCUGUUAGUCUACAAGAGCUUGCCAAAACUGUAUUCUGAACUUUUACAGGAUCCUGCUAUAACCCAGCAUACGUAGCCACCAUCCAGAUUUUGUUUUAAAAGUAGGUGUGGUUUAAUUUAUAUUGAAGGAGGUUUCCCAGGAAGUUCCUGGGCCAGAUUAGGUCUCCUCCUUCAUCUUAAACUCCAAUAGAAAUACAGAAACCUCUCUGCUUUGAUCUGAAUAUGUUUUAAGAGACAAUGUUAUGACUGGUGGUUACCGUUGCAUUUUAAGUUAUAAACAGUAUGUAGCCACUUGCCAGAAUUAACAAAUAGGUUAGAGUUACAUUACAUUCUUUUGAAUCUGAAAUUGAUAUUUUAUCACUUGUUUUGGCCUUUUUGCUGAAAUGAGAAUUUGUGGACGGUGGGGGCGCAAGAGAAAAAAAUGUUGGUUCCAUGUCUGUCAGGUAACUGGCAGAGUUAAAUUCCUAUGGCAUAUUUCUGGUCGCAAAAACAUCACUAAAUGUCUAAAUAAAGACCAAAACACUUCUAACAUUGAAUAUUGACAUAAAUGUGAACUGUACAUAUAUUUAAGACAGAAACUAAGCACAAGAUAAUAUUUACCCAGUUAUUCCAGCUCAGGGUGCCAGGUGAGAACCAGCCCUGGACAGGGCACCAUCCCAUUGCAGGGCGCACUCACAGUCACUCAUUCUGGAACCGUUUAGACUCAUCAAUGAACCUAGCAUGCAUAGCUUUGGGAUGUGGGAAGAGUACGCAGAAAAAAAACAGGUGUGCAUGGGGAGAAGGUGUGAACCAUAUAGACAGUGGCCUCAGUUGGGAGUUGAUUUUUUUCCCCCCUUACCAUCCUUCUAAUGAAAUGAUGUUGAAGGAAACAGUGUUAUUUGAGGAGCCAUUGUACAGGACUUUAACUGGGAUUUUGAAAGUUUAUAUCUAACACUGUCAUUUUGAUUAGAUUAAUUCAGGUUUGGUGAUAUGUUGCUUGCUUUUGUCUUCAGCUGUUAAGUCUUUUCAUGCCCUGGUCUAUGACAAACAUGGACCUGUUUUCUGUCACUAUCAUUUUGCUUUUACGCCCCCAACCUUUUUUUUUUUUUUUUCCGAGACAGGAUCUUGCUCUGUCACCCAGGCUGGAGUGCAAUGGCGCAAUCUCAGCUCACUGCAACCUCCGCCUCACGGGUUCAAGCAAUUCUCUUGCCUCAGCCUCCCGAGUAGCUGGGAUUACAGGCGCCUGCCACCAUGCCUGGCUAAUUUUUUGUAUUUUUAGUAGAGAUGGGGUUUCACCAUGUUGGCCAGGUUGGUCUCAAACUCCUGACCUCAGGUGAUCCGCUCACCUCGGCCUCCCAAAGUGCUGGGAUUACAGGUUUGAGCCACUGCGCCCGGCCCAACUUUUUUUUUUUUUUUUUUUUAAAGAGAUGAGGACUCACUGUGUUGCACAGCCUGGUCUUGAACUCUUGGGCCCAAGUGAUCCUCGCACCUCAGCGUCUCAAGUAGCUGGCACUUACAGGUGCAUGCCAAUGACUGGCUCAUUUUGCUUUUUCUAAAAAUUCAUAUUAAUGGAUGUAUACAGUUGUGUCUGGCUUGUUUCAAUUCGCAUAAUACGUUUGGGACUCAUUCAUGUUGUUUUCAUGUAGUUUGUUCCUUUUCAUUGCUUUCCAUUGCAUAAAUUUACCACAGUUUGUUGAGCUGAUGGAUAUUUGGGUUAUUUCCAGUAUUGGAGUAUUUUAAGUUUCUGUAGACCUUUGAGUACAGGUCUUUGUAUGAAUGUAUGCUUUUAUUUUCUUGCAUAAAUACACACAGUAGAAUUUUGGGGUUGUAUGAUAAAGUACAGCAGCUGUAUGCUUAACUUUAUAAGAAACUGCCAAACUGUUUUCCAGAGUGGCCGUACUGUUUUACAAAUUCCCAUCAGUAGUACAUGAGCGUUCCAGUUGCUCCAUAUCCUUGCCAACACCUGGUGUUGUCAGUCUUUAAAAAAUUUUGGUCAUUCCACUGAGUGUGGAAUGUAGUUUUAAUUUGUAUUUUUAAUUUUAAUUUGUAGUUUUAAUUUUCAUUUCCUUUUGGUUUGUGGAUUUGUACUUUGUGGCAUUUAUGCUAAAAGUACCAAGGAGGAAGAAAGUUGUUUUUUUCUUCAGAUUGUUAUCAUCUUGGUUUGUAACUUGUAUGUUCUCAGAACAUUAUUUGAUUCUCCACAAUCAGUAGCACAAUUAAUUUUAUAUUAAUUGGUUUUGUAGUUGUCCAGAACUCUAUUACACUUAAAACGUGAUCAAAUACUAUAAAUUAUUAUAUCAUUUAUGAUCACACCUGAUCAAUUAAGAGGAUUCGGGGAAGGUAAAACUUCAUGUAAAUCUUUGGAAAAUGGUUUUAACCUGUUUCUCAGCUAAUUAAAGAAUACGUAGCUAUAUUUCUUGUCAUUCUUUUUUUGGAAACUAUAAUAUGAAAGUUCAAAAUAUAAAAAAGAUACUUAAAAUUAGACAUUUGAUAGUUGGGAUAUGUUAUAGUACUUUGAAACAAAUUCUGUAAUAGUAUUCAGAAUUGAGAUGUUUAGCACACACUGCGUCAGUUAUGUUAAAUGGUGGGGAUGGGGUGUGGCAGGCAGUAGUGGAAUGUAGAAUGCUGCUGUAUGCUGUGUAAUGUAAGCAUCUCCGUUCCUAGUGGAGAAGUUGCGUCGUGUUCUCAAGAAGCACAGAGGGAGACAUUUGGUAAAGUACCAAGUAGUUGAAUGAAAUACAGUACAUAGCAGAUAAAUUUUGUAUAUACUAACAAAUCAGUAGCUAUAUUUGAUAUCCUGGGUAGCCGUAUUUGAUAUCCAAACUAUUAACACUUCAUUACCCUGAAGAGCUUCCUCCUUUCUUUUUGAUAGUAUUUUUUUUUUUUUUUUUUUGAGUCGGAGUCGUGCACUGUCACCCAGGCUGGAGUGCAGUGGCGCGAUCUUGGCUCACUGCAACCUCCGCCUCCCGGGUUCAAGGGAUUCUUCUGCCUCAGCUUCCCGAGUAGCUGGGACUACAGGUGCGUGCCACCACGCCUGGCUAAUUUUUGUGUUUUUAGUAGAGACUGGGCUUCACCAUAUUGGUCAGGCUGAUCUUGAACUCCUGACCUCGUGAUCCAGCCGCCUCGGCCUUCCAAAGUGCUGCAAUUACAGGUGUGAGCCACCAUGCCUGGCUGAUAGUAAUUUUUAAUCUUUAUGUGAUGAGGUGUGCAGGUCCAGAAAUCGUAACAUGAAUGGCAGUUAAAGGCCUUUGAGAAAGUAGGGGAGGGUGAUGGAUGCAUCAGCCUCGGCCACCCUCUAGUGGCUGCUCUGACCAUAUUGCAACUUCAGUUGAUCCUCUUAAGUGUACAUCAGGAGGGGGAAUGGCUGAGGGGCUUGUUGUUUUUUAUACAAAAUUCUUUUUUGUAUUAUAAAACAUCUGGAGUAAUCUAGAGGAAUAACUUCAGUAAGGAGUUACCUUAAAUAUCAACAUUGGUUAUUUGGGUACUAGGAUUAUGGAUGAUUUUAUUUUCAUAAUUAUACUUGAGUGUAUUUUCUAAAUUUUACGUAGUCAACUUUUUGUUCUAAGUCAGAGAAACAGAAAGGAAGACUCACUGAUCACCUCUGUGUGCCAGACACUGUUAUAUAUAUCAUUCCUAAUUCCUAAUACACGAAUUUGAGUUACAUUGAUUAGUAUAUACAAAAUUUAUGUCCUGUAUUUUCAACUUCACUUGGGGCUUUAAUGGAACACUAUCAUUCGCUAACAUUUUUGUGGCACAGACUUCUUGCUGAUGUUGUUUACCAGAGUGUCCUUUGAUUCUACUUCAGUCUUGCCUAGUAAAGUCAUCUUUCUCCCUUAAUGAAUAUCUCACCUUCUUUCGGGACCACUCACCAGUCUGUGAACCUUCAAAACAAAUACAUUCCAUGUUCUUAUUCAUGUUGACAUAUGUUUGAUAUAGUACAUACUGCCGUCUGUUGUAGUUAUUUGUGUGUAUUGCCUAUUUCCUAGCUUUGCAUCCUACAGCCCCAGAACAACACAUAGAAAGCACACAGUAUUUGCCUAAAACCAUAUAUUGGAAGCUUCUACCUGCCUCAGUUUGUGAUGUAAUGGUAUUUGACUUAUUUUAAUCAGUUGCUUGGCAUUGUAGCACAUUUUCCUAGAACCAGUAUUUCAAAUGGUGUGUAGGUGCCUAAGCCCUGAAAUACUGGUUUUAAAACUUAGCCACACAUUUAAAAACUGGAGAGUUAAAAAAAAAACAAAAAAAACCUCCAAUGUCCAGGUUACACCUCAUACACGUGGAAUCAAAGUAUUUGGAAUGGAAGCCAGGUAUCAGUAUUUUUAAAAAAGACACCCCAUGUUAUUUGGAUGUUCAGCAAAAGUUAAUGAACCACUACCCUAUUUAAUCUAUACUGCAUGGGUACUAAAGUUAAACUCCUGACAUUUAAAGUUUUGCUUUUGGGGAAAAUACUUUUCUCAAGCCAGAUGCAAGAGGUUUUGAUGGCAUAAGACCUACAGAUAACUAACAGGCUUAUUUAAGCCCAGGUAUUUAUUGUUAAAGGAGGUAUUUGUCCAACUUACUCUCAAAUAGUUCCCAAAAAAUGUUUGCAAGGGGAGAGAGAGAGAAUGAGAAUGGUAAAGCAAAUGGGGGCAAAAUGUAAACGGUUGCUGAAUUCUAUAAAGGCUGUAUGGGAUUGACUAAUAUUAGUCGUGCAACUUUUUUGUAAGUUUGUAAAACUUUUUAAAAGUUUUGUUAAAAAGAGAGAGAGAAUUUGUUAACACAGAUAAAUCACUAAUUGGUGAAAUAGUAGAGAUUUUUGUUUGUAAUUUUACUUUAUUAUUAUUAUUAUUAUUUUUUUUUUUUUGAGAUGGAGUUUCACUCUUGUCGCCUAGGCUGGAGUGCCGUGGCGCGAUCUUGGCUCACUGCAACCUCCACCUCCCUGGUUUAAGCGAUUCUCCCGCCUCAGCCUCCCGAGUAGCUGGGAUUACAGGCACCUGCCACCAUGCCCAGCUAAUUUUUGUAUUUUUAGUAGAGACGGGGUUUUGUCAUAUGAGUCAGGCUGGUCUUGAACUCCUGACCUCAGGUGAUCUACCCGCCUCAGCCUCCCAAAGUGCUGGGAUUACAGGCGUGAGCCACCAUGGCCAGCCCUAGAUUUUUGUUUUUAAUUUUUAAAAAUAUUGGAGUGCACAGAGUAUAUCUGGCUUCAAUCAUCUCUUUUCAUUCAUGUUGCUGUUUGACUGAAAUCCUCUUUCUCCUGGCGGAUGGGAUUGGCGGGUGGUCCUAUUUUCUAAAGGGAGGAGGCAUUUCCUAUUUAAUCUUGAGGAUACAGGGAAGAUGGUAUAGAGUUAAGCAUCAACCCACUUCUCUGUCUCUUCUUUUUGCCUCUUCUUUCUGCUUCAUUGGCACAAAAUACUGUUUCCAUUAAGAUGCUUAAAAGUGAUGCAGGUGCAGUUCUGCAAAUUUAGAAAAUAAUCAUUCGUUGGAAGAUACGUUAGAUCGUUUAAUUUUAACCUCCUGCUUUUUACCAAUAUGAUGACUAAACCAAGACUGGUAGAUGUAACCUUAUACUUUAUUUAAGGUCUACAAGGAGGAGGAGUAUAUAUUUUACUGUUUCUCUUGUUAUCUAGAAUUUAACAUGGGAUAUUUACCUUUAGGGAAAUCUUUUAUAUUAUAACUCUGCCCUGGAUGCUUAGUUAGUUAACUGUGCUUUUGUAGUUUCUUUAAGGAUUGUGGCUAGUAAUUAUGAAAAUAUACUAAAUCUCAUUACUAAUCAGAGAAAUGCAAAUUAAAACAAAAAUGAGGUAAUUUCACACCAUUUUAUUGGCAAAAAUUAAAAUGUCUGGCACUGCCAAAUGUUAAUGAGGAUGUGUGGGCUCUGCUAUUGGUGGGUGUAAGAAUUGAAUACUGCCUUCAUGAACAGUUUGGCAAUAUUUGAUAAAGGAGGCAUUCCUUUUGGCCUGACAUUUCUAAGUCUGUAUUCUGGAAAUGCUUGUUCAAAGGAGUCAGGUACAAGAGUAUUCAUCAUAGCAGUGUUUAUGUUAAUGGAAAACUUAGAAACAAGCCAACUCUCCAGCAGCAAGUGAAUAGAUUAAUUGUGGUUUGUUCAUACCCUAGAACACUAUGCAGCUAUUAGCAAGGAAUACAUCUCAAAAACAUGGUUGAAUUAAAAAACAAGUUUCUGAAUGAUGUGUAUGUAUGACACCAUUAUAUAAAGUUGGGCAACUUGCAAAAUCUUGUGUUUGUGGAUACUUAUUUGUAGAAAUAGUAUUAAAACAUGCAUUGGAAUGCAAACCCUGAACCAAAUUUAGGAUAGCAGUUACUUCUAGGAAACAGAGAAGGGUAUAGGAUUUGAGGAGUACACACAGAUUUUCAACUUGACCUGUGGUGUUUUCUUUCUUAUUAAAACUCUGAAGCAAAUAUAGUGAAAUGUUAAGAUUAGACAAAGCUAGCUAGUGGGUGCAGUUGUUGUGUUAUUCUCUGUAACUUUCUGUAUAUUUAUAAAAUACAUGAUUAGAUACAUUGAGGGUAGUAUGUUUAUAAUGGGCCAUACAUUCAGUCACCAGUGGUAACAUAGAACAGCAGACUGUGUCUUGCAGAUGAGACCUAAGACAGUAGUUCCUUAGACAGUAGUUCAGAACUUAGGUUUUGGAGUCAAAUAUACCUGGAUUAAAUUACAGCUUAUCCACUUGUUAGCCAUCUGACUUUGGGCUUUAGUGUGCACAUCUAUGAAGUAACAAUCAAACUUACCUCUUAGAGGUGGGUUGUGAGAUUUUAAAAAAGUAUGCUUCAAGUAAUACCCACUCAAUAUAUGAUAGCUUCAUUUAGCCUUUAACCACCUAGAUUAAAUAAUUCUUGUUUCAAAGAACCAUACUUCAGAGAACCAUGGGACGAUAUGUUACAAAUACAAUAUCGCUUCUUUUCUGUAUGACUGGCAUAAUUAAAAGUUUCUAAAAGGCAAGUCCAUGCCAGAACUUAAGAGAACACACUGGAGUUAUAUUCUGUACUGAGUUCCACCUACAAACUUAAUUAUGAAAGAUGGUUGAGGUUAACUUUGUUAUUGUGCUUUCCUCCUGGAUAAGCUUGCUUUUUAAAAGGAAAAAGCUCCUUUAAAAAUAGGUUCAGUUAAACUUACAAUUUUGCAGCAACCUCAAAUCCUCACUCUUAAUGGAUUUGUCCAGUGAAAAUGGUAAACAAGAACACAUACAUGGUAUGUAAAGGUAGAUAUAGGUACAACAAAUGAAAGUAUAUUUUCCUGGACUGGAAAAAUUCCUUUUUGCAAAGGUUAUGUUUUUGUUGAUCCUUUUCUUGAUUUUCAGUGCAGAAUUACUGUUAAUAUAUUUUAAUUGACCUUUGAGAGCUGUCUUAGGGAUCUCUAGAAAUAUUAUUAAAUAUAUUCAUAAGCCAGGCUCAGAUAUUCAUAAUCCAUAGCGAGGAAAACUCUUCCUUACUAUGUGUCAGAAAGAGAAGAAGGUAGAUGACCUCUCUCCCCCAAAUGUCUUGAACUUCCCUUUUCUAACCUGGCAUUGCUUGCUUGCCUUCUGACCAAAUUCAUCACAUUGGGAAGUGGAAGUAUACAUUGCUAUCUGAUGAGAUUUCAUUUUAAAAGUUCUCCCCAGUGAAAGCAUUAUAGGCACUUCAGAGUUGUGGGUGUUUGGCAGGUGUCUACAGCCAAGGAGAGUGAGGGAAAAGUGUUUCAAGCCCAGCUGUGUGGUAGAAAUGGAGCAUCUUCAUCCAGCAUCUCCCAGUGAAUUGAUCAUGUGUGGAAACACCAGUCCAAAAGAUUUUCAAAAGAAACAGCCAGACGAUGAUUCCGCUCCAAGUACAAGUAACAGCCAAUCAGAUUUGUUUUCCGAAGAGACCACCAGUGACAACAACAAUACCUCGAUAACCACGCCAACUCUUAGUCCCAGCCAGCAGCCGCUUCCGACAGAACUGAAUGUAACUUCACCGAGUAAAGAGGAGUGUGGGCCAUGCACAGACACAGCUCAUGUCUCAUUAAUCACACCAACAAAAAGAUCCUGUGGUACAGAUUCACAGUCUGAGAAUGAGGCUUCACCAGUAAAACGGCCACGACUACUUGAGAAUACGGAACGGUCCGAGGAAACCAGUCGAUCUAAACAGAAGAGUCGACGUCGGUGCUUCCAGUGCCAAACCAAACUGGAGCUGGUGCAGCAGGAAUUGGGAUCGUGUCGCUGCGGUUAUGUGUUCUGUAUGUUACAUCGCCUCCCCGAGCAGCACGACUGCACAUUCGACCACAUGGGCCGUGGCCGGGAGGAAGCCAUCAUGAAAAUGGUGAAGCUGGACCGGAAAGUGGGGCGCUCCUGCCAGCGCAUCGGGGAGGGGUGCUCCUGAAGGCCAGGCAUGGCCACCACGUGACGCUGUUCUUAGUUCACUAAUGUUAGCCUUAUUUAGGACAAAGUCAGCCAGACACCUUGUACUGGGCACGCGUCAGACUGCAGCCAGUCCGUUUCCUUUCUUUAGCCAGCCAUCCUGGUACUGUAGUUUAGGGGUUGAUGGUGGUUGAAAUUGAUUUCUGGCUGGUUACUAAGGUGCCUGCUAGCCAUUGUAUAAAAUUAAAACAUGAAGAAUAUUUUUUUUUUGAGCAUGGCUAGUGGAUUUAAAACAACACAUACCUGUCACUGCUGGAGUCAAACUUAUAAAAAGCCUUAAGUGGAAAGUGUUCCAGACGGAGACUCUGAGUUAAUAGAGGAGUAGAAGCUGGUGUUAAAGUUCCCACGACGCACAUGGCUUUGCCAGAAACUCUGUUUAAUGAUCGGCCUUUCACCUCUUCACUUAUCCUUAGUCCCAGUAGCCAGGAUACCUGAUGGCCACGUGUGCCUUGGCCACGGGAGGCUGCUGAGAUUGGCCACGUGGCUGGGCUGGGUGGUGGCCUCACUCUCCCACAGAGCUGGAAAUGGGGGGUGGGGGACAGAUUCUUACGGAAAUUUUUUUACCUGACUUGCUAUGAAAAAACUCAUCACACAAGAAGAGAAACAGUAACCUCACUUUGAAAAUUAGCUCCACUCAAGACUAGUCCACGAACGAGACCCGCCUUUUCUACACAGGAUCCAAGGUCACGAGAAGCAGCCAGAGUGCCCCGCCUCCGCCGGCUCUGGUCUGCCAUUCGCCAGUGCAGGGAUCUGGCACGGACCAGAUGUGGCGAAUGGCAGCACAGCGCGGUGGCUGGGUCUGCACACUGGCCUCUGCAGCCAGAUUUCUAUAUUGGGAGUUUUUUAAAAAGACAUUUCAUAGCCAACAAGAAUCAGUAGAAGUGCUGGGAGCAGCAGCUGGGGAAGCUGCCGCCCACGGGCUCUGCCCCUUCCAGCUGGAGCCGCCCGUGCCUCCAGGGGCCAAGAGGAUGAUGUCGUGGCCUCCAUUCUCGUUUCUAUGCAGCCCCAUAGUCCAAGGACACCCAGUCCACAUCUACCAUAUAGCAAGUUUAGUAAGGGAAGGCAGCAUACGUCCCAGGGACAGUGGGUUUGGAUCUGUCUAGAACAGCGGUUUGUGGCUGUGGCCCAGCUCCGAGAGUGAUAUUUGCUCUGGUAGGUGAGGGCCUGAGGGUACAUUUCUCCACCUGUGCCCCCUCAUGUUCACAGAGGAUUUCAGCAGCUGCAACUGCGCACGCCAGGUGGGGAAGGGUGGGGGUGGGCCUGGUUGCCCCAUGUUAGGAAAUCACUACCAGUCAGGUGGGGCUGGGGCUGGGUGGACAGGAUCAGGAUUCCCUUGAAAGCCCAGGCAGGGUGAGCAGUCCCAGUGGUCCUAGUGCCGCAUCAGAUCCAGGUGGGUGAGGGCAGGAGGCCCCUGCGGAGGCAGCGUGGAUCUGCCCACACAUAGGCUACUGGAAUAGUUUAACCCAGCAACUUUCCUUUUUAUAAAACAACAAAUGGUUCAACUCUGUCUGCAAAUUAACAGCUGAACACCUGCAACUGCAAAUGUUUUUUGAUCCGACGUACUGAAAUAGGAAGUCAUGCUCUUCCCACCCUCCACCCACCAGAGUGGAACCCGCUGCAAAAUCCCCAGCCUUAAUUCUUGCUUCAGGACCCAGACCGGUGUCUUGCUCUAGGGCAACCCAGGGCAGAGGGGCCAGGUCUGCCCAGCGUUUACCACUGCUGUCAAGCCACAGCCCUUGGCCACCAUACGGGCCAUCCUCAGUGAGGCAGCCCCCCAUAGGCUUCCGCCAAGCUCUGGUCCCGAAGAGGCUGUGCGAGCCCUUCCCGGCCCUCCCCAGGGCCCCCCGCCCCCUCCUCUGCCUGCUGCGUGGAGGCAGCCAUGGGAAGGAGCCCAGGGGAGCUGGCCUGGGGGAGCGAAGCCCAUGUUCGCUUCCUGACUUAGAGCUGGGGGGGGUGGGGGGUGGGGCUUGUUCCCCUGCAGUAUCUGUUCUGUGAAGUUUGUUAAAUGUAAGGAAAGCUUAAAUUCUUGUAUCUUUAAAAGAGAAAAUCUUAUUUAACCCUUUUGUGUUCUAGAUUUACUUACACACAUAGCCUAGAGCUCAGUUUUAGUUUUAACAUUGUGAAAAUAUUAAAAGAAUCUUGUAACUUUAUUCUUUUUUCUCCUGCUGAAAAAAAAAAUUAAACCAAUCGUAUGAAA